GGGGAUUGCUGAUUGAGCAAGCUGAGUGGCUGCCCCUCAGAAUCUUCUGUAGGCCUUUCUCUUGCCUUCUUUUAUUCACAACUGAUGACACUGCAUAUCUUCCCCUGUUCUUAUUGGGAGAAGGCCUUGUGUGUCACCAAGAGGUUCUCAGAAGGGACCUGUCAGUUUUUGGUUAAAAGAACCCGGAAAGAGAAGGACUAUGGGGGAACUGAUGGCGUUCCUGUUACCUCUCAUCAUUGUGUUAAUGGUGAAGCACAGCGAUUCCCGGACGCACUCUCUGAGAUAUUUUCGCCUGGGCGUUUCGGAUCCCAUCCAUGGGGUCCCUGAAUUUAUUUCGGUUGGGUACGUGGACUCGCACCCUAUCACCACAUAUGACAGUGUCACUCGGCAGAAGGAGCCACGGGCCCCAUGGAUGGCAGAGAACCUCGCGCCUGAUCACUGGGAGAGGUACACUCAGCUGCUGAGGGGCUGGCAGCAGAUGUUCAAGGUGGAACUGAAGCGCCUACAGAGGCACUACAAUCACUCAGGGUCUCACACUUACCAGAGAAUGAUUGGCUGUGAGCUGCUGGAGGAUGGAAGCACCACAGGAUUUCUGCAGUAUGCAUAUGACGGGCAGGAUUUCCUGAUCUUCAAUAAAGACACCCUCUCCUGGCUGGCUGUAGAUAAUGUGGCUCACACCAUCAAGCAGGCAUGGGAGGCCAAUCAGCAUGAGUUGCUGUAUCAAAAGAAUUGGCUGGAAGAAGAAUGUAUUGCCUGGCUAAAGAGAUUCCUGGAGUAUGGGAAAGACACCCUACAAAGAACAGAGCCCCCACUGGUCAGAGUAAAUCGCAAAGAAACUUUUCCAGGGGUUACAGCUCUCUUCUGCAAAGCUCAUGGCUUUUACCCCCCAGAAAUUUACAUGACAUGGAUGAAAAACGGGGAAGAAAUUGUCCAAGAAAUUGAUUAUGGAGACAUUCUUCCCAGUGGGGAUGGAACCUAUCAGGCGUGGGCAUCAAUUGAGCUUGAUCCUCAGAGCAGCAACCUUUACUCCUGUCAUGUGGAGCACUGCGGUGUCCACAUGGUUCUUCAGGUCCCCCAGGAAUCAGAAACUAUCCCUCUUGUGAUGAAAGCUGUCUCUGGGUCCAUUGUCCUUGUCAUUGUGCUGGCUGGAGUUGGUGUUCUAGUCUGGAGAAGAAGGCCCCGAGAGCAAAAUGGAGCCAUCUACCUUCCAACACCAGAUCGAUGAUUGCAGAUCCCUCUUUUCCAGUUCUCCUUCCUCUAGGAGCCAUGUUAUCCUCUGUCCCCCAUAGAGUCAAGCCUAGUGCUUGAAGGUCCUGACGACACCCACAACAUACAUGAGAGUAAUGGGAUUGAGCAUUUAUGGCAGCAACAGAGGAGCCACAAAAUGUUCUUUGUUCUUUGGCUCCAAAAAGACUGUCAGCUUUCAGUCUCUUUUGAUGGACUGUUUUAUCAGAGUUGACUUUAAAUACAGCUUGUCUCAUGACACAACGCUUCCCUACAUUCUAUUUGUCAAUGAUGAUUUGCAACUAGUUGGAGAUUCUCAGAGCAGGAAGGAAUCUUUUCAACCAGAGCAGGAACUGUCUUCUGCAAUGCCUUGGACUUGAGCCUCCAGCCUCCACUUGAACACCAUGUGAAGGGAACCUCAGUACUUCAUAAAAUGGCCUUUCUCAUUCAUCUUUCAUGGGAACAUUUAUUGUACAAGCGCUUUGAAUAUCAUGGGCACCAUGACUGUGACCCUACAGGUAGGAUUGGAUCACUCCAUGAGAGUAGCCGGCAGGUUUCUACAAUGGCCUGGGAAUGGACUGAUUAUUUUUAUACAUUUUCUGGCCUGAGAGAAAGCCAAAGUCCCCUGCUGUUCACAGCAACCCUGCCUGGGAGCUUGGAAUCUUGGUAAUCUGCCCGGUUGGAUCUAUGGAGGUAGUCUCACCCUUUUUGUCUUUUGUGGGAAAUUAAGAGAAAUAAUUAUCAGACAUAUCAUCACCUCCAGUGGAACUACAGAGACCUGGACCCAGCUGCACUAUUUUAAUGUAAAAAUAACAGUAUGGCCAGGUGCAGUGGCUCACGCCUGUAAUCCCAUCACUUUGAGCAGCCAAGGCGGGCGGAUCACGAGGUCAGGAGAUUAAGACCAUCCUGGCCAAUAUGGUGAAACCCUGUCUCUACUAAAAUACAAAAAAUUAGCUGGGCAUGGUGUUGCGUGCCUGUAGUCCCAGCUACUUGGGAGGCUGAGACAGGGGAAUUGCUUGAACCCGGGAGGCAGAGAUUGCAGUGAGCCGAGAUCACGCCACUGCACUCCAGCCUGGCGACAGAGUGAGACUCUAUCUCAAAAUAAUAAUAAUAAUAAUAAUAAUAAUAAUAAUAAUAAUAACAGUAUAUUUGGUGUCAGGAGAGGGCUCAAUUCUCAUUUCUGCCUUUCCUGUGCUGGCUCAUGGUAGCUGGGCAUGACUUGCCUUCCUACAUAGGUUGUCUUCAUACAUAUGCACUGGGAAUCAAUAAAAGCCCAUGGUGAGAAUGAACAUCCCCUUAAUGUUCCUUACUAUCCCCAACCCCUGAGGCCUCACCUACUGCCCUGCCAUGUGGAGCUACUUGCCCUGGGGCUGCCAGUCACACAUUCCUCGGUCCUACUUCUCUGACCCCGUUUGACUCUGCACCUGAGCCCUAAUGCUUACUUCAGUGACCUGAACUUUGACAAGUGGCUUUUGUCCUGCACCUCAGGUUUGACCUCUGCUCUCCCUUGACCUUGACUGUGACAUUUGACCUUUGGCUUUAAUCAUUACAGCCUCAGAUAAAGGUACCUUCAGCCCGGGCACAGUGGCUCACGCCUGUAAUCCUAGCACUUUGGGAGGCUGAGGCAGGCGGAUUCCCUGAGCUCAGGAGUUCAAGACCAGCCUGGGCAACACGGUGAAACCCUGUCUCUACUAAAAUACAAAUAAUUAGCUGGGCAUGGUGGCAUGUGCCUAUAGUCCCAGCUACUUGGGAGGCUAAGGCAGGAGAAUCACUUGAAUCUAUAAGGCAGAGGUGGCAGUGAGCCGAGAUCACACCACUGCACUCCAGCCUGGGCAACGGAGCAAGACUCUGUCUCCAAAAAAAAAAAGAAAGAUACCCUCAGUGUGCCAGGCCUCUAAGAGCUCACCUGCCAGGCUUCCUCCUUGCUCCACUGUCCCAUGUAAUUCCAUAUAUGAAGCUACCACUGUACAUCUCUCUUUUCCGGUGCCUGUUGAGUUGCAUAGAAGCACAGUUGUGUUUAUUUUGUUUUUAGGGUUGCCAUGGGCAAUUUCCGUGCCACUUUUAAGCAGUGUUGCACUGUGAAGAGAAUGUAGGCAAGUUUAUUUCUGGAAUGGUUUCUUCUUACAAUCAGAAUAGUUAGGAUGUAAUAUAUUUUUGGGUGGGCAUUUAAAGUGAAAAGGUACAUAUUUACAUAGACACAGGUGAUAAUGUAUCUAUGUAAAUGCCUUUUGAUUCUGCAACUGCAGGAUACUCUCAUCAAAGACACAGAUAAAAAGCCUCUGUGUUUCCAAGGCCUUGCCCUACACCUAACACAUAAUAUGUCCAAAUGGAUGAAGAGGAGGCAAGGACAAGGAUGUGAUGACAAAACAUUCUGUUAUGCACUUGUAGCAUUUAUGUUUCUUCCUGGGGGAUUUUAUAAUACUAAAAGAAUCAUAAUAUAAAGAGAUGAUUAAAAAAAAAAUACUGCCGGGCACGGUGGCUCAUGCCUGUAAUCCCAGCAUUUUGGGAGGCCGAGGUGGGCAGAUCACCUGAGGUCGGGAGUUCGAGACCAGCCUGACCAACAUGGAGAAACCCUGUCUCUACCAAACAUACAAAAUUAGCCGGGGAUGGUGGCGCAUGCCUAUAAUCCCAGCUACUCGGGAGUCUGAGGCAGAAGAACCGCUUGAACCCGGGAGGCAGAGGUUGUGGUGAGCCGAGAUCGCGCCAUCGCACUCUAGCCUGGGCAACAAGAGUGAAACUCCAUCUCAAAAAAAUAAAAAUAAAAUAAGUAAGUAAUACCUAAAAUUCUGCAACCUUCAUUUUACUAUAGAUGGUUGAAGAUUAUAUUACUUCUUAAUUGUUUUAGCCUUGUUAUUGCUUCAUUACUUCAUGGUUGUUGAGUACAGAUGCUCAGUAAUCAUAACCUAUGAAAUAUUUGACACCAUGAUCUAAACAUUAAAAACAAAUAACUGUGCUAUUGCCACAGCUAUGUUUUGGCUUUGAAUUUUCUUUACUGAAUAUUUUGGAUCAAGAACACUAGAUGAGAAACCUGUUCAACUCUGUUCUUUUUUUUUUUUUUAACUCCACUGUAUUUAUUACCUGUUUUUGUUUUUUUUGUUUGUUUGUUUUUGAUGUGCAUAUAGACCAAGAUGUGGUAAAUUUAAAUGGCAGAUGUUUUUGAUGUGGUACAUUUAAGGGAGAGAAAGCAGUUUAAAGAGCAGGGUGAAAAAUCCAACAAGACUCCAUCGAGAGUUUCUGAGCUCUCCCAUCAGGGGCCAGUCCUCCUUUCCUCUCUCCUCUUACUCCCAUGAUUUCCAAGUUGUGAUCCUUUCCUUAUUUCUGAGGAAUGACUUGGUUUCUCCUCUUCUUUUUUUGGCCUGAGAGAAGAUGUUUUUGCACUUGUAGCUAUGAGGAACAGAUUGUCCACUAGGGAGGCCAGCUGAUCAUUUUCUGCCAGAGUCACACAGAGCAGUCACACCUUAUUUUGAAAACCACUGUCUGGGGUCUUUGUCCUCACAUAUGCAGGUCUAGUGUCCCCACAAAGUGAUCAGAUGGAUAUAUAAAGUGGAGUGCCAAUGUAUUAAUUUACUGUGAGAAACACAAUUGCUAAGUGGGUCAGAUAUCUGUCUCAGCUGGUCAGUACACCUUCCAGCAGGAAAAUCUACAUAAGAACAACUAAAUCACAAUCUGUAGAGUGCUUGAUGACCCCAGAAUUGGUGCAAGGGGACACAUUCUUGCUUGUUAGCACCUGCUCUCUGGAGUUUGCUAUUUUCUCACACACAGUGUAUUAGUUCACAGAAUGUUCUCCAAGGAGGACAGGGGGCUUUGCCCAUAGCCAUGUGCUGUGGGCAGCAGAGCUAGGAAGAAGCACAGGCAUCUCCCAGCCCAGGUGUUUCCCACUUAACUGCAUUGCCCUUUUCAUCUUUUUUUUUUCCCCAAUAGCUUCAGGACAUUCAGUACAUUGUGCUUUUUAGAGGUUGAUGAUUCCACUGCCUGAGCUGCCUUCACCUCUCUUUCUUUGGAAAUUGCCAUCUUUGAGCAUUGUAUGUCUCUGUAACAUCUCUGCAUCUCCUUUUCACUCUGGCCUCCCUUUCUCCAUUGUCCUUCUAGCUUCUGGUUGCCCCAAACCCCACAGACUGUGUAACAAAACCCAAAACCUAUUGGUUUAAAACAAUACCCAUUUUAUUUUCUUUCAUAGUUUCUAUGGGUCAGGAAUUUGGAUAUGGCUUGGGUAAGCAGUUCUGGCUUCUCAUGGAGUUGGAGGCAAGUGGUGGCUGGAACAGAAAUGGGGCAGCCAGGGGUGGUGGCCAGGCAUCAGCUACAUCUCCUCCAUGUAGUCUCAGGAACUCUCCAUGUAAUCUCUCUGUGUGGGUUGGGCUUCCUCACAACAUGGUGGCCUCAGGGCAGUCACUGCUUACAUGGCAGCUAGCUUCCCUCAGAGUGAGUAUCCCAAGAGAUCACAGUCAAAGUGCAUAGCAUUUAUAUAAUCUAAUCUUGGAAGUCACAAAAUGUCAUUCUUGUGAUACUCUCAUUGGUGAAGAAGUCAUAAAAUCCUGCUCAGGUUCAAAAAGAGGGUGUAUAGAACCCAACACUCAAUAGGAAGAUUGUCAGAGUUACAUUGUAAGAAGAGCAUGUAGUUGGGAGAUAUCAUUGUGGCCAUUUUGGGAAAGAUGCAACAUGUCACAAUGUCAUGUUCUCCAUCGUCUCCCCGUUCCACCUUGUACUGGUUUCCAAGGGUAGUCGUUUAAAAGUACCACAAAAACUGGGUGGCUUGGAACAACAGAAAUUUAUUGUUUCACAGUUCUGGAGGCCAGAAGUUCAAAAUGAAGUGUUGGCAGAAACAUGCUGCCUCUAAAGGGACUGGGAAAGGAUCUGUUCCAGGCUUCCCUCCUAUCUUCUGGUUGUUCCUUGCCUUCUGGCUGCGUAACUCUAGUCUUCAUUUGGUGUUCUCCCUGCAUGCAUGGCUUUGUGUCCAAAUUUCCUUUUUUCAUGAGGCCAUCAGUCAUACUGGAUUAGGGACCCACUCUACUACUGCAGGAUGACCUCACCUUCCCAAAUUACAUCUGCAACAACCCUAUUUCCAAAGAAGGCCACAUUCUGAGGUACUGGGGGUUAUAACUUCAACAUGAAUUUUUUGGAGGAAACAAUUCAACUCCUAACACAUCUCUACCCAACCUCUGUAGGUUCCCUCAAUCCACCAAAAUUUUUUGGCUCCACUGGAUUAUCUAGCAGUUAGGAAACCAAGAUCAUUAAAUGAAUUCACCGCAACUACAGUGAGACUGACUACCUUAGCUUACCUCUGUGAAAGGAGUUAAGCCAAAGGAAUCUGUGGAAUUUUGGAGAGUUUGGGAGCAUUUGGGGGCAGGAGGCAAAUGUUCUUCCUUUAAAUCACAACACUUAGUUCUCUUCCAUUUAUAAGACUCACCCCUCCAUCCCAACCCCUGCACCACAGGACAAGGAAGUGUUCUUGGUCUUCAACUUUCAUCCCUGAUGGUGAAAGCAGUUGCUCCUGACCUAUUUGCCCACCAGCUUCUCCUCUGGAGCCUGAGGCUUCUGAUGCCUGCCUGGCUGGUUCUCAGUAAGAAGGUCAAGUUCAACCAGAGGGGAGAUGCUGAUGCCUUUCAGUACUUAAAUAUGAGUUCAGACCCUGGGGCCUGGACAUAAGAUUUGGGGUCCCCUGGAUAUAAGAUUUCUGAAAACACUCAGACUGUGGAGACCCCUGCUGAGGGAGAAGCCCCAAACUGUGGCUUCAGGGGAAUGCACCAAGGCUCUCAUUGAGGCCACCUUCUCCAACAAGCUCCCCUCCUGCUUCCCCAUGGCUGGCAUGGCUGAGGAAAAAGGACACUGAGCACAGCCCGUGCAUGAGCGGCUUGCCAUGCAACAGGAUAAAACCCAUAAUGCCACUCAGCAAGCCUUGGUUGUAAAUCUAGUUUGAUUACAUUUGUAAUCAAAUGAUGGCCAUUUGUUCUGUUUCUGGUUUGUGAACCAACUGAAGACAUAAGCAGGGCCUCAGCUAACCCACAAAUAGCACAUGUGUGCAAACUGGAAAAAUGAACCCUUCUUCUGGGAGGACGCCAGCCCAGGCCAGGUCACCCGGCUUGGCCAGCAGAACACAGAGUAGAUUUUGGUCCCGUUUGUUCCCCAGUGGGGUAUCUAUCCUUGUGCAGGGCACAAGCCUACAUGGUGGCUCUGGUCAUAUCAUUAGAAAAUAGACAGAAAUGGGCUGCACACCAGAAUGAAUGAAUUGAAUUGAAAGGGAGGAGUGAUGGUGGAAAAAAAAACAAGUCAAUUCAUUUAGACUGGUAGAACCAGAACCACUGUGUAGUACAUCCAAACGGUUAAAAUUCCCUGGAAGAUGUUACAUAAUCCUAUCAUGGUGUUUAUUUAUGGAAAUCUAUUUUAAAAAUUUUAUGUAAUACUGCACAGUCUGUUUGCAUGAUGCCUUGUACGUAGUAGCAACUCAGUAAAUACUUUUUGAAUGAACUAGUAUAGUAUUUUAAUUAGCUAGUCUUCAUGUACUGGUACAAAAGAACAGUGUCAUCUUACAGCUGAAGUCAUAGAGGGGAAAUAUCCCACUCAAGAUCAUAUAACAUUCCAGGUACUCAGGAUGAAUGGUUUGAGGACUGGUCUGAAUUCUUCAAAGGUUUCAGCUGUAUUAACAUUCUCCAUCUAAUAAACUUUAUCUUGUCAUUGCA